GUCACCGGUCUCCAGCCUGGGCGACAGAACGGGACCCUGUCUCAAAAAAAAAAAAAGAAAAAAGUGAAAUGCAUAGUGUACAAGUGGACUUUACCCUGUGACCGCCCUUCGUUGACACCAGCUUGCCUGGUCUGUGCACCCAGGACUGCUGGCCAGAGGAGCAGUGUGCUGCUGCCAACGCCCUGCAGACAGGUAAAGGUUGUUGCUGUUGAUGCAGAGUUGAAUGUCUUCUAUGAGGAAAGUGUGCAUUUUGACAGAGAUCUUCCAGAAUUUGGGACUCAGGGUGGUGUUCAUGUGCACAAGGAUGGGCUGACGGUCACUUCUCCAGUACUAAUGUGGGUCCAGGCACUGGAUAUCAUCUUGGAGAAGAUGAAGGCUUCGGGCUUCGACUUCUCUCAAGUCCUAGCCUUGUCCGGGGCGGGCCAGCAACACGGAAGUAUAUACUGGAAGGCUGGAGCCCAGCAGGCACUGACAAGCUUAUCACCAGACCUCCGGCUACACCAGCAGCUGCAGGACUGUUUCUCCAUCAGCGACUGCCCGGUGUGGAUGGACUCCAGCACCACAGCCCAGUGCCGCCAGCUGGAGGCUGCUGUGGGUGGUGCUCAGGCUCUCAGCUGCCUCACGGGGUCCCGUGCCUAUGAGCGUUUUACAGGGAACCAAAUUGCAAAAAUUUACCAGCAGAACCCCGAGGCCUACUCACAUACGGAGAGAAUUUCUUUGGUCAGUAGCUUUGCUGCUUCCCUGUUCCUUGGCUCUUACUCCCCUAUUGACUACAGUGAUGGUUCUGGAAUGAAUUUGUUGCAGAUACAGGAUAAAGUCUGGUCCCAGGCUUGCCUUGGUGCCUGUGCACCUCAUUUAGAGGAGAAGCUUAGCCCACCAGUACCAUCAUGCUCAGUUGUGGGAGCCAUUUCUUCCUACUACGUCCAGCGCUACGGAUUUCCUCCAGGAUGCAAAGUGGUGGCCUUCACUGGGGACAACCCAGCGUCGCUGGCAGGCAUGAGACUGGAGGAAGGUGACAUUGCGGUCAGCCUGGGCACCAGUGACACCCUGUUUCUCUGGCUCCAAGAGCCCAUGCCUGCCCUGGAAGGCCACAUCUUCUGCAACCCGGUUGACUCCCAGCACUACAUGGCACUCCUGUGCUUUAAAAAUGGCUCCCUCAUGAGAGAGAAGAUCCGCAACGAGUCUGUAUCCCGUUCCUGGAGCGAUUUCUCUAAGGCACUGCAGUCCACAGAGAUGGGCAACGGUGGAAACCUGGGUUUUUAUUUUGAUGUAAUGGAGAUCACCCCUGAAAUUAUUGGACGUCAUAGGUUUAACACAGAAAACCACAAGGUUGCAGCAUUCCCUGGGGAUGUGGAGGUUCGAGCACUAAUUGAAGGACAAUUCAUGGCCAAGAGGAUUCACGCAGAAGGCCUGGGCUAUCGAGUCAUGUCCAAGACAAAGAUUUUGGCCACAGGAGGAGCAUCUCACAAUAGAGAAAUCUUACAGGUGCUUGCAGAUGUGUUUGAUGCCCCGGUGUAUGUUAUAGACACUGCCAACUCGGCCUGUGUGGGUUCUGCAUACCGAGCUUUUCAUGGUCUUGCAGGUGGAACAGAUGUGCCCUUUUCAGAGGUUGUGAAGUUAGCUCCAAAUCCCAGACUAGCUGCUACCCCAAGCCCGGGAGCUUCUCAGCGCCGCUGGGUUGGAGUCUCCACGACCGAGCUGGUCUCGGCAAGUGGUGCCCAACACGGGGGCUCGAACCUGGGUCGAAUAGUCGCCAGAGCGAUGGUUAGAAAAUGUGGAACUACACUGGAGGACACCCGAGUACUGUUAAAGCAAUCCUCAUGGUUUUCCUUUUGUAAUGGGACUGUUAAAGAAUGUUGCUGUCUCCAGUCAGAUGAUGCCAGCGGUAUGGCAGGAUCACUUCUAGGUAGGUCUAAUUUACAUUUAAAAGGAGUACAAGUACAAACAGGAGUCAUUGAUUCAGAUUACAGUGGGGAAAUUCAAAUUGUUAUAUCUACUUCUGUUCCCUGGAAAGCAGAGCCAGGAGAGUGUAUAGCACAACUCCUGAUUGUGCCAUAUGUGGAAAUGGGGAGAAGUGAAACUAAACAGACAGGAGGAUCUGGAAGUACAAAUAAGCAAGGGAGAGCAGCUUACUGGGUAAAUCAAAUUACUGAUAAACAUCCUACCUGUGAAAUAACUAUUCAGGGAAAGAAAUUCAAAGGGUUGGGAGAUACAGGAGCGGACGUUUCAAUCAUUUCUCUACAGCACUGGCCGUCUGUGUGGCCAAUUCAAUCCGCUCAAUUUAACAUAGUUGGAGUUGGUAAAGCCCCUGAAGUAUAUCAAAGUAUUUAUAUUUUGCAUUGUGAAGGACCCCAUGAACAAUCUGGGACUAUUCAGCCAAUUGUAACUUCUGUACCUAUAAAUUUAUGGGGGAGAGAUUUAUUACAGCAAUGGGGAGCACAAGUUCCCCAUUACAUAGAACAAUUAUAUAGCCCUCAAAGUCAGCAUGUGAUACAAGAGAUGGGGUAUGUGCCUGGCAUGGGAUUAGAAAAAAAUUUACAAGGGUUAAAAAAACCAGUUCAAGCGGAAGGAAAAAAUUCUUGUCAGGGUUUAGGGUAUCAUUUUUGAUGGCGGCCAUUGUUAAGCCUCCGGAACCUAUACCUUUAAAAUGGUUAACAAGUAAGCCAAUUUGGAUAGAACAAUGGUUGCUGAGUAAAGAAGAACUGGAGGCUUUAGAGGUCUUAGUUACUGAACAAUUAGAAAAAGGACAUAUAGCUCUAACGUUUCCCCCCUGGAAUUCUCCACUCUUUGUUAUUAUUAUUAUUAUUUUUCUUAAGAUGGAGUCUCGCUCUGCUGCCCAGGCUGGAGUGCAGUGGUGCGAUCUUGGCUCACUGCAAGCUCCGCCUCCUGGGUUCAUGCCAUUCUCCUGCCUCAGCCUCCCGAGUAGCUGGGACUAUAGGCGCCCACCACCACGCCCGGCUAAUUUUUUGUAUUUUUAGUGGAGACGGGGUUUCACUGCAUUAGCCAGGAUGGUCUCGAUCUCCUGACCUUGUGAUCCACCCACCUUGGCCUCCCAAAGUGCUGGGAUUACAGGUGUGAGCCACCAUGCCCAGCCCUCCAGUCUUUGUUAAGAAAAAAUGUGAUAAAUGGAGAAUGUUGACAGAUCUUAGAGCCAUUAAUUCGGUUAGACAACCUAUGGGAGCAUUGCAGCCUGGACUGCCUUCUGCUGCUAUGAUUCCAAAAAAUUGGCCUUUAAUAGUCAUAGAUUUAAAAGACUGUUUCUUUAUUAUCCCCUUAGCUGAGCAAGACUGUGAAUGGUUUGCAUUUACAAUUCCUGUGGUAAACAACCUGCAGCCUGCUUAGCGUUUUCAUUGGAAAGUGUUGCCACAAGGCAUGUUAAACAGUCCAAUGAUUUGUCAGACUUAUGUAGGACAAGCAAUUGAACCUACUCGUAAAAAAUUUUCACAGUGUUACAUUAUUCAUUAUAUGGAUGAUAUACUUUGUGCUGCCCCCACUCAGGAAAUAUUACUCCAAUGUUAUAAUCACUUGCAAAACUCGAUUUCUCAUGCUGAUUUAAUUAUAGCUCCUGACAAAAUUCAGACUACUACUCCUUACUCCUACUUGGGGACCUUAGUAAAUGACACUACCAUUGUGCCACAGAAAGUAACCAUACAUAGGGAUCAAUUGAAAACAUUGAAUGACUUUCAAAAAUUACUGGAAAACAUUAAUUGGAUAUGACCUGCUCUAGGCAUUCCUACCUCUGCCAUGAGUAAUCUCUUUUCUAUCCUUAGAGGAGAUCCCAGUCUCACAAACCCUUGGCAAUUAACAAAGGAGGCUGAGGCAGAGUUACAGCUGAUUGAAAAGCAAGUGCAUAAAGCUCAAAUAAAUAGAAUAGAUCCAGAAAAGAUCCAGAAAAGAUUGAUUUUUCCAACUCAGCAUUCACCUACUGGUGUUGUUGUUCAAGAGCAAGAUCUUGUAGAAUGGCUUUUUCUUCCACAUACUAAUCCAUGGACUCUAACUCCUUAUUUGGAUCAAAUUGCUACUCUGAUAGGAAAUGGGAGAACUCAAAUUGUUAAAUUACAAGGAUAUGAUCCUGGAAAAAUUUUUGUUCCCCUUACAAAGGCACAAAUACAAAAAGCCUUUAUAAAUAGUCUUAAUUGCAAACCCAUUUAGCUGAUUUCAUAGGUGUUCUUGAUAAUCACUUUCCAAAGACAAAAUUAUUUCAAUUUUUGAAAUUAACUAAUUGGAUUCUCCCUAGAAUAACUAAAUUUAAACGAAUUGAAGGUGCGGAAAAUGUUUUUACAGAUGGGUCUAGUAAUGGUGAAGCUUCUAACUCUGGAUCAAAAAGUAAAGUUUUCCAGACGCCCUAUACUUCAGCUCAAAAAGCAGAGCUUGUAGUUGUAAUUGAGGUGCUGACGGUUUUGAGAUGCCUGUCAAUGUAAUUUCUGAUUCUUCAUACGUGGUUCAUUCCACACAAUUAAUUGAAAAUGUUCAGUUACAAUUUCAUGCAGAUAAACAACUGAUGACUUUAUUUACCCAAUUGCAAACAGCAGUUAAGAGUAGAAUGCACCCUUUUUACAUAACUCGUAUUAGAGGUCAUACACCUCUUCCAGGACCUUUGACUGCAGGAAAUCAAAUUGCUGAUUGCCUAGUUGCUAUGGCAUUAUCUAAUGCUAGACACUUUGAUAAUUUAACCCAUGUUAAUGCCUCUGGUCUCAAACGCAGAUACAGCAUUACCUGGAAAGAAGCUAAAGCUAUUAUCCAGCAAUGCCCAACUUGCCAAAUGGUGCAUUCCUCGUCUUUUACAGGAGUAGUUAAUACUUGAGGAUUGGAACCUAAUUCUCUUUGGCAAAUGGAUGUCACACAUGUUCCCUCGUUUGGGAGACUAGCUUAUGUACAUGUAUGUGUAAAUACAUUUUCUCACUUUGUUUGGGCUACAUGCUAAACAGGGGAAUCUUCUGCCUGUAUUAAAUGGCAUCUUCUGCAAUGCUUCACAGUCAUGGGCAUUCCAGCUUCAGUUAAAACAGACAAUGCUCCAGGCUAUACUAGCCAAGCUCUAGCUAUAUUUUUCUCUAUAUGGAAUAUUAAACACAUUACUGGCAUCCCAUAUAAUUCACAAGGACAAGCCAUUGUGGAAAGAAUGAAUCACUCCCUAAAACAACAAUUACAAAAGCAGAAGAGGAGGAUCAAUGAUUAUAGGAAUGGUGAUUAUAGGACUCUGCACAUACAACUAAAUCUAGCAUUAUUAACUUUAAAUUUUUUGAGCCUGCCUAAAGGCCGGAUGCUACCAGCAGCUGAACAGCAUCUACAGAAA